GCAGACCCUGGCAGAAGGGGCACGGGGCAGGGUGUGAGUUCCCCACUAGCAGGGCCAGGUGAGCUAUGGUGCUGCACCUACUGCUCUUCUUGCUGCUGACCCCACAGGGUGGGCACAGCUGCCAGGGGCUGGAGCUGGCCCGGGAACUUGUUCUGGCCAAGGUGAGGGCCCUGUUCUUGGAUGCCUUGGGGCCCCCCGCGGUGACCAGGGAAGGUGGGGACCCUGGAGUCAGGCGGCUGCCCCGAAGACAUGCCCUGGGGGGCUUCACACACAGGGGCUCUGAGCCCGAGGAAGAGGAGGAUGUCUCCCAAGCCAUCCUUUUCCCAGCCACAGAUGCCAGCUGUGAGGACAAGUCAGCUGCCAGAGGGCUGGCCCAGGAGGCUGAGGAGGGCCUCUUCAGAUACAUGUUCCGGCCAUCCCAGCAUACACGCAGCCGCCAGGUGACUUCAGCCCAGCUGUGGUUCCACACCGGGCUGGACAGGCAGGGCACAGCAGCCUCCAAUAGCUCUGAGCCCCUGCUAGGCCUGCUGGCACUGUCACCGGGAGGACCCGUGGCUGUGCCCAUGUCUUUGGGCCAUGCUCCCCCUCACUGGGCCGUGCUGCACCUGGCCACCUCUGCUCUCUCUCUGCUGACCCACCCCGUCCUGGUGCUGCUGCUGCGCUGUCCCCUCUGUACCUGCUCAGCCCGGCCUGAGGCCACGCCCUUCCUGGUGGCCCACACUCGGACCAGACCACCCAGUGGAGGGGAGAGAGCCCGACGCUCAACUCCCCUGAUGUCCUGGCCUUGGUCUCCCUCUGCUCUGCGCCUGCUGCAGAGGCCUCCGGAGGAACCGGCUGCCCAUGCCAACUGCCACAGAGUAGCACUGAACAUCUCCUUCCAGGAGCUGGGCUGGGAACGGUGGAUCGUGUACCCUCCCAGUUUCAUCUUCCACUACUGUCAUGGUGGUUGUGGGCUGCACAUCCCACCAAACCUGUCCCUUCCAGUCCCUGGGGCUCCCCCUACCCCAGCCCAGCCCUACUCCUUGCUGCCAGGGGCCCAGCCCUGCUGUGCUGCUCUCCCAGGGACCAUGAGGCCCCUACAUGUCCGCACCACCUCGGAUGGAGGUUACUCUUUCAAGUAUGAGACAGUGCCCAACCUUCUCACGCAGCACUGUGCUUGUAUCUAAGGGUGGGGGGUCUUCCUUCUUAAUCCCAUGGCUGGUGGCCACGCCCCCACCAUCAUCAGCUGGGAGGAAAGGCAGAGUUGGGAAAUAGAUGGCUCCCACUCCUCCCUCCUUUCACUUCUCUGCCUAUGGGCUACCCUCCCCACCCCACUUCUAUCUCAAUAAAGAACACAGUGCAUAUGACUUGA